UUUACUCAGUGCUUGUGUAAAACAGAAAAGCCUUCUUAUUCCUUGGAUUUUUUUUUUUAUUGUUUUAAUAGAAAAACAAAGUUUUGAUCUGAAAUGUCUUAGGUUAUUUUUCCUGCCUUUAUCCUUAAAUCUUAAGUUUCUGAUCAUGCAGUAAAUAUUGCUUGGGCACUUAUUAUGUGUCAGAUGCUGUGCUGUGAGAGUUACAAAGCAAAGCAAGACAUAGCUACUGUUUCCAAGUCGGAGGGCUGCCAUUUAAUGAUCCGAAUAUGGAACCAGUAGACUAUGGCCUGUGAAGGCCCAUGCCGAAGGAGAACCAAGAAGAAUUGCCCUGUACAUUAUAUUGACGUAAAACUUUUCACCUUUUAAAAAUAUAUUAUUUCCUUAAUACUUCCAAUUUUUUAAAAGCUCUAGAAUAUUAUCUGAGAAAGCCCAUGUGCUUCCUAAUUGUUAAAUUCUGAAGUAGACGAUAAGGUCACUAAAGGAUGCUAAUGAGAUGAAUGGAAAUGGGAAAUUUGAGAAGAAUUUUAUAGCUAUUUAAACACUCCUCACUGCUUAGGUUAAAUUUUAAAAAAUUAUUGGGGAAGUGACAUUAGCUCUUUAAGUUCUUUUGAUAUUUUGAAGACAUUUCAGUUAGAAUGAACUUUGACAAGGAGAAAUUCCCCCCAGGGAGUUUUAUUUAUAGCACAUGAGAAAGGAAUUCUGUGUUCUCACCAGGAUUUCUACAAAGCAAGGAUACUUUUUAAAAACUUUUCCUUGAAAAACAUCUUGUAUUCAGCAUUAAAGCCAGCGAUGCAUUAAAAGGACUUGCCAAGUAGAAGAAAGCACUUAUUGGAGAGGGGGAGUAGAGUCAAGCAAAUAAACCUGAGAUUUUUAGGAUCAUUUUUAUAAGUCUUGAAUUCGUUGAUGAUGUUAACAAAAAAGUCCGUGGGGAAGGUGUACAGGAGACUGUGGUCCCGGAGGAGUCCAGAGUCGGGCAGUGUGGUGUUUUCAUGUUGACGGGUGGACAAGUCACCUGUCUAACUGUGGUGAGAGCAACAGGCCUCCAAAGGAAAGAAGUUGUUUCCGAGUUUGUGACUGGCACAGUGACCUCUUUCAGUGGGAGGUUUCUGACUGGCACCACUGUGUGCUUGUUCCUUACGCUCGCGGUGAAGUCAAGCCUCGGACUGCAGAGUGUGUGACGGCUCAGCAUGGACUGCAGCACCGGAUGGUGCGCUGCAUUCAGAAGCUGAACCGAACUGUGGUUGCAAAUGAAAUAUGCGAACACUUUGCCCUUCAGCCUCCUACAGAACAGGCUUGCCUCAUUCCUUGUCCCCGGGAUUGUGUAGUAUCUGAGUUCUUACCAUGGUCCAACUGUAGCAAGGGAUGUGGGAAGAAAUUGCAGCAUAGAACUCGCGCGGUCAUAGCUCCCCCUCUCUUUGGUGGUUUGCAAUGUCCAAAUCUGACUGAGUCAAGAGCCUGUGAUGCUCCCAUUUCCUGUCCUCUUGGGGAAGAGGAAUAUACAUUUAGCCUUAAGGUUGGACCAUGGAGUAAAUGCAGACUGCCUCAUCUUAAAGAAAUUAAUCCAAGCGGAAGAACUGUUCUGGAUUUUAACUCUGAUUCAAAUGAGCGAGUCACCUUUAAACAUCAAAGUUACAAAGCACAUCAUCAUUCGAAGUCUUGGGCAAUAGAGAUAGGUUAUCAAACCCGGCAGGUUUCGUGUACAAGAAGUGAUGGACAAAAUGCUAUGUUAAGCCUUUGCCUUCAAGAUUCCUUCCCAUUGACUGUUCAGUCCUGCAUCAUGCCCAAAGACUGUGAAACCUCCCAGUGGUCCUCCUGGAGCCCCUGCUCCAAGACAUGCCGUUCAGGGAGUCUCUUGCCAGGAUUUAGGAGCAGGAGCCGGAACGUGAAGCACAUGGCUAUUGGAGGUGGAAAGGAGUGUCCUGAACUUCUUGAGAAAGAGGCCUGCAUUGUUGAAGGAGAACUUCUGCAGCAAUGUCCCAGGUAUUCCUGGAGAACUUCUGAAUGGAAAGAAUGCCAAGUCUCUCUCCUCCUCGAGCAGCAGGAUCCCCACUGGCAUGUGACGGGACCCGUGUGUGGCGGUGGGAUCCAGACCCGGGAGGUGUACUGUGCCCAGAGCGUACCAGCAGCUGCCGCACUGAGGGCCAAGGAAGUCUCUAGACCUGUGGAAAAGGCAUUAUGUGUGGGACCCGCCCCGUUGCCCUCUCAGCUCUGCAAUAUCCCUUGCUCUACGGACUGCAUAGUAUCUUCCUGGUCAGCCUGGGGCCUGUGCAUCCAUGAAAACUGUCAUGAUCCUCAGGGGAAAAAAGGAUUUAGAACGAGGCAGCGCCAUGUCCUCAUGGAAUCUACAGGGCCUGCAGGGCAUUGCCCUCAUUUGGUGGAGUCUGUUCCUUGUGAGGAUCCAAUGUGCUACCGAUGGCUGGCAUCAGAAGGGAUCUGUUUCCCUGAUCAUGGAAAAUGUGGCCUGGGACAUCGUAUUCUGAAGGCCGUCUGCCAGAAUGACCGCGGAGAAGAUGUAUCAGGGAGUCUUUGCCCAGUUCCCCCUCCUCCUGAGAGGAAGUCUUGUGAAAUUCCCUGCCGAAUGGACUGUGUGCUGAGCGAGUGGACGGAGUGGUCAUCCUGUUCCCAGUCCUGUUCAAAUAAAAACUCAGAUGGGAAACAGACCAGGUCAAGAACUAUCCUGGCACUGGCUGGGGAAGGUGGAAAGCCAUGUCCCCCUAGUCAGGCUCUCCAAGAGCAUCGUUUGUGUAAUGACCAUUCCUGUAUGCAGCUUCACUGGGAGACAUCGCCUUGGGGCCCUUGUUCUGAGGACACAUUGGUAACUGCCCUUAAUGCAACCAUUGGCUGGAAUGGAGAAGCCACGUGUGGUGUAGGCAUUCAGACUCGGAGAGUCUUCUGUGUCAAGAGUCACGUGGGACAAGUAAUGACCAAAAGAUGUCCAGAUUCUACUCGACCUGAAACUGUGCGCCCCUGUUUUCUCCCAUGCAAAAAAGACUGUAUUGUGACUGCUUUCAGUGAGUGGACACCCUGCCCAAGGAUGUGCCAAGCAGGAAAUGCCACAGUAAAACAGUCUCGAUACAGAAUCAUCAUCCAAGAAGCAGCCAAUGGAGGCCAGGAAUGCCCAGAUACCUUAUAUGAGGAGAGAGAGUGUGAAGAUGUUUCCUUGUGUCCUGUAUAUCGGUGGAAGCCACAGAAAUGGAGCCCUUGCAUCUUAGUGCCAGAGUCUGUCUGGCAGGGAAUAACGGGCAGCAGUGAAGCCUGUGGAAAGGGGUUACAAACAAGAGCUGUCUCAUGCAUCUCUGAUGACAACCGGUCAGCAGAAAUGAUGGAAUGCCUCAAGCAGACAAACGGCAUGCCUCUCCUUGUGCAAGAAUGCACAGUCCCAUGUCGAGAAGACUGCACCUUCACUGCUUGGUCCAAGUUUACGCCCUGCUCCACGAACUGUGAAGCCACAAAAAGUAGGCGGCGACAGCUCACAGGGAAAAGCAGAAAGAAGGAGAAAUGCCAGGAUUCUGACCUUUACCCUCUAGUGGAGACAGAACUAUGUCCUUGUGAUGAAUUUAUAUCCCAACCUUAUGGAAACUGGUCAGAUUGCAUUCUUCCAGAAGGCAGAAGGGAGCCUCACCGAGGACUGCGGGUACAAGCAGACAGCAAAGAAUGUGGAGAAGGCCUGCGCUUUCGAGCAGUAGCCUGUUCUGAUAAAAAUGGAAGACCUGUUGACCCCUCCUUCUGCAGCAGCUCUGGUUACAUUCAAGAAAAAUGUGUCAUUCCCUGCCCAUUUGAUUGCAAGUUAAGCGAUUGGUCUAGUUGGGGGUCUUGCAGUUCAUCUUGUGGAAUUGGAGUGAGAAUUCGAUCCAAAUGGCUAAAAGAAAAACCUUACAAUGGAGGACGACCAUGUCCCAAACUGGAUCUCAAGAAUCAGGUACAUGAGGCAGUCCCAUGUUACAGUGAGUGCAAUCAGUAUUCCUGGGUUGUAGAACACUGGUCUUCAUGCAAAAUCAACAAUGAGCUGAGGUCCCUGCGCUGUGGAGGAGGAACACAAUCUAGGAAAAUCAGAUGUGUGAAUACUGCGGAUGGUGAAGGUGGAGCAGUGGAUAGCAACCUGUGCAACCAGGAUGAAAUUCCCCCAGAAACCCAGUCCUGUUCUCUUAUGUGUCCCAAUGAGUGUGUCAUGUCUGAGUGGGGACUUUGGAGCAAAUGCCCACAGUCAUGCGAUCCCCACACAAUGCAGAGAAGAACUCGCCACCUGCUAAGACCAUCACUGAACUCAAGGACUUGUGCUGAAGACUCACAGGUGCAGCCUUGCCUCCUGAAUGAAAAUUGCUUCCAGUUCCAGUACAAUCUAACAGAGUGGAGCACAUGCCAGCUGAGUGAAAACGCACCCUGUGGUCAAGGCGUCAGGACCCGCCUGCUAAGCUGUGUGUGCAGUGAUGGCAAGCCAGUCAGCAUGGACCAAUGUGAGCAGCAUAAUUUGGAGAAGCCCCAGAGAAUGAGCAUUCCCUGCUUGGUGGAAUGCGUGGUCAACUGUCAGCUCUCAGGGUGGACGGCUUGGACAGAGUGUUCACAGACCUGUGGCCAUGGAGGUCGAAUGAGCCGGACUCGAUUUAUCAUUAUGCCAACCCAAGGAGAAGGACGGCCAUGCCCCACAGAGCUUACCCAGGAGAAAACCUGCCCAGUGACCCCCUGCUACAGCUGGGUCCUUGGCAACUGGUCUGCAUGUAAAUUGGAGGGUGGAGACUGUGGGGAAGGAGUUCAGAUCCGCAGCCUUUCCUGCAUGGUCCACAGUGGUUCAAUAUCUCAUGCAGCUGGACGUGUCGAGGAUGCACUGUGUGGAGAAAUGCCCUUUCAGGACAGCAUCCUGAAGCAGCUGUGUUCUGUGCCUUGCCCAGGAGACUGCCAUUUAACAGAAUGGUCAGAGUGGAGCACAUGUGAAUUAACCUGCAUUGAUGGAAGAAGCUUUGAGACUGUGGGCCGCCAGUCUAGAUCAAGGACUUUUAUAAUUCAGUCUUUUGAGAACCAAGACAGCUGCCCCCAACAGGUUCUAGAAACACGCCCUUGUACAGGAGGCAAAUGUUAUCACUACACAUGGAAAGCAAGUCUUUGGAACAAUAACGAACGAACUGUAUGGUGCCAGCGUUCAGAUGGCGUUAAUGUCACAGGAGGCUGCUCCCCUCAGGCCCGUCCUGCUGCCAUUCGGCAGUGCAUUCCAGCCUGCAGAAAACCUUUCUCCUACUGUACACAGGGUGGAGUCUGUGGUUGUGAGAAGGGCUAUACAGAGAUAAUGAAAUCAAAUGGUUUCCUGGAUUACUGCAUGAAAGUACCAGGCUCAGAGGAUAAAAAAGCUGAUGUGAAAAACCUUUCUGGGAAAAACAGACCUGUGAAUUCAAAAAUACAUGAUAUUUUUAAAGGAUGGUCUCUUCAACCACUUGAUCCAGAUGGCCGAGUAAAAAUUUGGGUUUAUGGCGUUUCAGGUGGCGCUUUUCUCAUCAUGAUUUUCCUAAUAUUUACUUCCUACCUUGUUUGCAAGAAGCCAAAACCACAUCAAAGCACACCUCCCCAACAGAAGCCUCUGACCUUAGCCUACGAUGGAGACUUAGACAUGUAAUCUGAAAAAGAAAUCCAAAUGUAGACAUCAACUGCCUUAACCGCUUUCUCUUUUGUAGCUCUCAGACUUCUCAGUUUUUUGAGGAAUCUCAAGAUGUGAUAUAUUGGGCAGAAUACAAAUAUUGCAAAAGUAAUAUUGCCUCAACUUCAUUUGGACAUGGAGUCAAGGAUUAUUAGGUCUGCCAUUUUGUUUUCAAGUUGUUUGUGGGUGUGUUUUAUUUUUUUGGUUUUCCCAAGGGACCUGAAAACCCUUCUCUUCCUGUUUGGAACUGGGAGGAAGAAAACAUGAUGGAAUUCCCACAGACUUGAGUAAACUUGAUCUUCAGCAGCAUAAUGACAAUCCAGAGGAAAAUACAGUCAAGGCAUUUACUCUAAAUGACGAGUCUGACACUGCAUUGUUACGCACUAUAUUAGUGCAAAGUCUUUAUUCUUCCCAUACUUCAACACUGAGUUUUCUAGAGUUUACUUUGGUUUAAAGACUUUCAAAUUGGAUUGCCUAUUUUUCAUGAACACAGAGAGAAUGGAUUACCAUUUCAGAAAUUCUCUGAGUUUUUAACCUUUAAAUAUUGUAUUUUGUUUUGUAGCCAGGGGAUGAUGGCGCUUCAUGGGUUGCAGCUACUGAAAAUAGCAGCGUGUGUGUAAUUGCUGGACUAGAUGAAAGCUAGGUCAUUUCUGAAGGGAAUGUGUACUGAAUGUUAGAGUGUACAAAUGAAAUAUGUGGUUAAAUUGGAGAAUGAGGUAGAUUAUUUGAUUACUAAAACUGUAUUUUAACAAAAACUUAUCCAUGUAGAUAUAGCAUUAACCACACACAGUUGUAAUUCAGUUUAAUGAUGACAAACUCUGCUUUUGUAAUUUCAAUUUUCUUAUCUGAAUAUUUAUAAAUUCUUCUUUCAAAUUUAAUUAUCUGACCUCAUUUAAUAUACAUCAAACACCGAUCCUGUUUGUACAAAGUCUUGCUUUUAUAAGGUUUCAAUAAUAUCUAAAACAACACAUUAAAAAGCUGAGACCAUUUUAUGAAGAUAAUUGUUUGUAAUCAUAGGUGUUGAAAGUAAAAAGGUGCCAUCUUGUGGUAUUGACUUGUAUUUAUAACAAAUAAACUGCUCAAGAGACUGCA